GGUAACCGCGUCGCAGUCGCCGAAGAUGGCGGGGCGAAGUCUGUGUCUCACGAGAAGCAGCGUUCCAGGGACUCCGUUCCCGCCACCCGUUCAGCAACCCUCUACACCUGGACCCGACCUCCUCGCCUUGGAGGAAGAAUAUAAGCGUUUAAAUGCAGAAUUGCAGGCAAAAACAGCUGACGUGGUUCAACAAGCUAAGGAAAUAAUAAGAGAUCGGCAAGAAGUACGAUCUAGGCCUGUUUCAACACAAAUGAAAUCAUGUGAUGACGAAGAUGAUUACAGUUUAAGAGGUCUGUUACCAUCUGAAGGGAUAGUUCAUCUUCAUUCAGAAACUAAGCCAAAGACCAAAAACAUUGAUCCUGUAAACAAGGUUCAAAACAAAUUACACUCUGCAAAUAAAGGAAGGAAAACAAAUUCAAGUGUUAAAUUGAAAUACUCUGAUGUCCAAACUGCCGACGAUGUUGCCAUUCCAGAGGAUUUCUCAGACUUUUCCCUUGCAAAAACAAUUAGCAAAAUUGAAGGGCAACUGGAGGAAGAAGGCUUACCUGAAUAUAUAGAUGAUAUUUUUUCUGGUGUUAGUAAUGACAUUGGAACAGAAGCACAGAUCAGAUUUCUAAAGGCCAAACUCCAUGUUAUGCAGGAGGAAUUGGAUAAUGUUGUAUGUGAAUGCAAUAAAAAGGAGGAUGAAAUUCAGAAUUUAAAGUCUCAAGUAAAAAAUUUUGAAGAAGAUUUUAUGAGACAGCAGCGAACAAUUAAUAUGCAACAGUCUCAAGUAGAAAAAUACAAAACUCUUUUCGAAGAAGCAAACAAAAAGUAUGAUGGAUUACAGCAACAGUUGUCUUCAGUAGAAAGGGAAUUAGAAAAUAAAAGAAGACUGCAAAAACAGGCUGCAAGUAGUCAAAGUGCCACAGAGGUUCGCUUGAAUAGAGCUCUAGAAGAAGCAGAAAAGUAUAAACUGGAGUUAAGUAAAUUAAGGCAAAAUAACAAGAUGCAUAUUGAAGCUGCCAAGAUGCUAUCUUUCACUGAGGAGGAAUUUAUGAAAGCACUUGAAUGGGGAAAUUCAUAAGUGAUCUACUUCAGUUAGUCUCUAUGACAGAUGUCACCCAGUCACCCAUUAAAGAUGGAAGUGACACAUGGACACAGGGAGAGGAACAUCAUCACACACCAGGGCCUGUCGGGGGGUGGGGGGGACAAGGGGAAGGGAGAGCAUUAGGACAAAUACCUAAUGCAUGCAGGGCUUAAAACCUAGAUGACGGGUUGAUAGGUGCAGCAAACCACCAUGGCACAUGUAUACCUGUGUAACAAACCUGCAUGUUCUGCACAUGCAUCCUGGAACUUAAAAAUAUUAAAAAAAUAAUUAAAAAGAUGGAAUGACAGUAUUAUUUAUUAGGGGUAGCCUUAAGUCUUCUCUCACCCUAGAUCUCACUGGUCACCAAGCCCCAUCAAUUCCGUAUCCUUAACAUCUCUCGGGUGGAUCCCUUAUCUAUUUGCAUGGGUUUCACCACUUGUCACUGGGAUUAUUAUAAUAACUUACUUACUGAUCUCCCUAUCUCCGAGCUUACUCAUCUCUUAUCUACCUUCAAUGCUCUCACUUGAAUCGUCUUUCAAAGUACAGAUCUUAAUAUACAGCUUUUCAAUCUUCAGUGGCUUCCCUUAGAAAAGCCCACCUUCUUAAAAUAGCAUGCAGGGUGUUCAUGAUCUGUUUCUCUCUCUGCCAUACCAAAACAUCCAUAGCUCUAUAACCUAUUAUCACAUGUACAUGACAUAUUUAUAAUUACUUUUUAUAUAUUUUUCUUAACCAAGACCAUAAAUUCAUAAGUGACAUGGACUUAGUUUUAUUUACCUUUUAUGUUCUCAAUACCAACCAGUGUUUAGCACAUAGAAAGCAUCAAUAAAUAUUUUCUAGAAGCAAAAAUGGUCAGAAAAUUUAUAUAUAUAUUAGUAAACAUACUAACAUUGUCUGGCAUAUAAAGCUUCUCAGUAAAUGUUUAGUGGAUGAUAGAUGAGCUAUUGCUGUUUAAUGAUAAUGACCAAAAAAACCCCACAACUUUUUCUUACUUUGUCUGCAAGGAAUUGUUGGCGACGCUCUUCAAUAAGUUUUUCCACAGCCCUCCUGUGUUCCAGCUGCUUCAUUCUUUGUUUCUGAGCAUUCAUUAAUUCUAUUCGAUCAUCCUCAGCAAAUUUAGCUAGCAUAGUUUUUCUAAAGUUCUCCUCUUCCUCUUUUGCAGCCUGUAGCACUAAUUCCUUCAAGGCCAUUUGUUCUUCAAAAUCUUGCUUCAUCUCUUUUUGCUUUCUCAAUUUCUUUUCUGCUUCUUCCUAAACAAUACAGCUGAAAGUUAAUUUAGUAACUAUUUCCUUACACCAGAUUUAUAAGGAAAGAGUGAUAGAGUUUGGUUAAAUUUAGUAUUACAAUAUGAAAUCAUACAAACUGAAAAAGUAAGGCUUUUCAUGAUAACUUUGUCCAUCCCUUUAAAACUAGCUGGAUAAAGAAUAUGCUUACAUUUGGAUUGUUUUCUGUUACUCAUGAACAAAUUUUAAUUUAUAUUUACCAUCUUGUUUCUCUACUCAGAAUUAACACGUAACUGCUUUGGAAAGAGCUGUUACAAAAGCCUUUUUUGCACACCUGAGUUUAUUCAUCUAAAGUCUAUGGUAACUAUGAAUCAUUCUAGAAUCUUGCUUACAAAAGCUGUCCAAACCACCCAUAAGUAUUUUUCAGUUUCCAACCUCCUCCUCAAAAUCAAAGCUGCACUUACCCAUCUCUAGUCUUCUAAUAUUCCCUUCAUUCUCCAAAAUUCUCUAAAAUUUAAAAACAAUUAUCUAGCAAUGACAAUCAGUACUUCUUUAGGGAAAUUCAAAUAUAGUUGGAACAGUUAAGUCCUUUCCUAUAAGCUUUUAUUUUCUGAACAUUUUAUUAUGAAAAAUUUCAUACAUACUAAAAAAUAUAAUUUUACAAUGGUCACUCACUUCUAAAUAAUUCAUGGGCCAAAGAGGGAAUGCCAAGGAAAAUAAAUACAUUGUAGUUAAUAAAAGUGAGACAGCAAAAUUUGUGAGAUGCUGCUAAAGCAGUUCUGAGAAACAUUUAUAGCACUAAAUGGAUACAUUUAGGAAAAUGUAUAUAUAUAGCACUAAAUGCAUGUAUGUAGGAAAAGUCUCAAAUCGAUAAUCUAAGCCCCCACUUCAAGAACCUAUAAAAAGAACUGUAAAGUAAACCCAAAAUAUGCAGAAGGAAAAACAUAAUAAAACUGUAGAAAUCAAUGGAA